AAGCCAGGGCAGAAUGCUUGUGAAGUAGCAACUAAAGUGGCAGUGUUUCUUCUGAAAUUCUCAGGCAGUCAGACUGUCUUAGGCAAAUCUUGAUAAAAUAGCCUUUAUCCAGGUUUUUAUCUAAGGAAUCCCAAGAAGACUGGGGAAUGGAGAGACAGUCAAGGGUUAUGUCAGAAAAGGAUGAGUAUCAGUUUCAACAUCAGGGAGCGGUGGAGCUGCUUGUCUUCAAUUUUUUGCUCAUCCUUACCAUUUUGACAAUCUGGUUAUUUAAAAAUCAUCGAUUCCGCUUCUUGCAUGAAACUGGAGGAGCAAUGGUGUAUGGCCUUAUAAUGGGACUAAUUUUACGAUAUGCUACAGCACCAACUGAUAUUGAAAGUGGAACUGUCUAUGACUGUGUAAAACUAACUUUCAGUCCAUCAACUCUGCUGGUUAAUAUCACUGACCAAGUUUAUGAAUAUAAAUACAAAAGAGAAAUAAGUCAGCACAACAUCAAUCCUCAUCAAGGAAAUGCUAUACUUGAAAAGAUGACAUUUGAUCCAGAAAUCUUCUUCAAUGUUUUACUGCCACCAAUUAUAUUUCAUGCAGGAUAUAGUCUAAAGAAGAGACACUUUUUUCAAAACUUAGGAUCUAUUUUAACGUAUGCCUUCUUGGGAACUGCCAUCUCCUGCAUCGUCAUAGGGUUAAUUAUGUAUGGUUUUGUGAAGGCUAUGAUACAUGCUGGCCAGCUGAAAAAUGGAGACUUUCAUUUCACUGACUGUUUAUUUUUUGGUUCACUGAUGUCUGCUACAGAUCCAGUGACAGUGCUGGCCAUUUUCCAUGAACUGCACGUCGACCCUGACCUGUACACACUCUUGUUUGGAGAGAGUGUGUUGAAUGAUGCAGUGGCCAUAGUCCUUACAUAUUCUAUAUCCAUUUACAGUCCCAAGGAGAAUCCAAAUGCAUUUGAUGCCGCAGCAUUCUUCCAGUCUGUGGGGAAUUUCCUGGGAAUCUUCGCUGGCUCAUUUGCAAUGGGGUCUGCGUAUGCCAUCAUCACAGCACUGUUGACCAAAUUUACCAAGCUGUGUGAGUUCCCGAUGCUGGAAACCGGCCUGUUUUUCCUGCUUUCUUGGAGUGCCUUCCUGUCUGCCGAGGCUGCCGGCCUAACAGGGAUAGUUGCUGUUCUCUUCUGUGGAGUCACACAAGCACAUUAUACCUACAACAAUCUGUCUUCGGAUUCCAAAAUAAGAACUAAACAGUUGUUUGAAUUUAUGAACUUUUUGGCGGAGAACGUCAUCUUCUGUUACAUGGGCCUGGCACUGUUCACGUUCCAGAAUCAUAUCUUUAAUGCUCUUUUUAUACUUGGAGCCUUUCUAGCAAUUUUUGUUGCCAGAGCCUGCAACAUAUAUCCCCUCUCCUUCCUCCUGAAUCUAGGCCGAAAACAGAAGAUCCCCUGGAACUUUCAGCACAUGAUGAUGUUUUCAGGUUUGCGAGGAGCGAUCGCAUUUGCCUUAGCUAUUCGGAACACAGAAUCUCAGCCCAAACAAAUGAUGUUUACCACUACGCUGCUCCUCGUGUUCUUCACUGUCUGGGUAUUUGGAGGAGGAACAACCCCCAUGUUGACUUGGCUUCAGAUCAGAGUUGGCGUGGACCUGGAUGAAAAUCUGAAGGAGGACCCCUCCUCACAACACCAGGAAGCAAAUAACUUGGAUAAAAACAUGACGAAAGCAGAGAGUGCUCGGCUCUUCAGAAUGUGGUAUAGCUUUGACCACAAGUAUCCUUUGAUAAUAACGAUCUCACAGAUCCUGCUGCAGGCAGAGAAUUACUUUAAGCUCUUAAUCAUUGAAGUGUGCACUCCUGCUCUUCAAGAAACACCAAAAGAACUCCUAACAGCAGUUGGAUAUUAACAAGGAGAAAAGAACAAUUAUCAUUUGGGACUCCAAGUGCCACUUUAUGUCACUUUAAAGAAUGAAUAGACUUCCAGCUCCACUCAGCUGCCUGUUCACAGUUACAAAGCAAUGGUAAAUAAUCGUAAGUAAAUGGAAGGUGUGAUUUAGGAGGGUGAAAUAGUAUAACGACUCGAUGCUUUCUCUUGCUUUUCUGUGGCAAGGCAAGCAGGACAGCUCCUGCCACGGGUUUGGCUUAAAUCUGGAUCUGUGACUUACCAAAUUAAAAAAAAAAAAAAGGUCCUGGAACUAUUUAUUAAAGUGGACACACAACAAACUACCAAAACAUUAUUUUUACAAGGAGAGAAUGAUCAUAUCAUGAGUCAUGGUUUAAUUUGCUCUCUAGUGGUUUUAUUUAACCAAAGGAUCAUACCUGUUCGUGCCAAUAAAACUUGAGUGGUUUUAAUAGAAAGUACAUCUUUCCAUUUUCUCAGCCAUGCCAGUUUACAAGGAGCCAUCUGAGCUCUACUCCUGAGAAGAUGUGUUGAUAUGGUGGAUAUGGGCAGGACUUUCCGUUUGCACUCAUAAUUCACCCCAAAGGGAGGUUUUAUACUCACUCUGAAAGGGGUCUAGACCUCAGCCAGUGAAGGCUUUGAUCUUGGGCCUGAAACCAUCUUAUCCAAACACACAUUCAUUUAAUCUUGCAACUCAAGAGUGACGCACCCUUCCAAAGUGGUUUGGGAGGACCAAGGGGACAGGGUUGGGGCUUGCAGGAGAGACUCACAGAUAUGCCUGAGGAGCCAGUUAUCUGUGAUACCCAGUCUCAGGAGAGCAGCUUUGCCUCUCAGUGAGGCUGGAGGGCAAUGUAAAGCAUUUCUAGUGCAGGCAGUCUCCUCUAGGGCUUUCCAGGGGGAGUGAGAUUGUAUAUACAGGAAAGUAUAAGGGCAAACAAGAACUGCCCUAGGGAAAUCCAGACAGGCUGAGAUCCAUGGCUGCUGUUUUUCCCACCUUUCCUUCCAGUGUCCAGCCCAGUGCCCACCCGUCUCCUACACCCCUGUCCCUAAGGCCACCGUCUUGUGCCAUUUCCUGACUAUAUUACUAUCAACUAAGUCCAAAAUAAGGUGGAGGUUUCAGAUAAUACCUUUCCCAGAAGAAUUUGUAUGUUAACAUAAAGCCCUAAAUCCCUUUCAAGUCUCAAUUCAACAAACAUUGAGGAGACUCAUUUCUGCCUACUGGGCAUUAAGCAUUUGUGGAAACAAAGAGGAAAGAGACUUGCCCCUCCCUCAAGGAGCUCACAGUCUAACAAGAGAGGAGAUAUAUAGUCAAAUAAUUCUGAUAUAAUCAAUGGAAACAGAAAGGUCUGUGGAAACCCCAGUGAAGAAAUUCCUGUGUUUGUCACAGGAAUAGUGACAAAGAAGAGGUACUAUUUGAAUUGGGUCCUGGAUCCAGUAUCCAUUAGGAUUAUGUCUGACUAUGUAUAACAGGAAAAUCCAAAUAACCAUGGAUUAAUGAAAAUAGUGGUGUUUAAUCUCACUAAAAGAAGUCUGGUAUUAGACAAUCUAUGUAUGGUUAACAGAGCUCCAUGAUGCCACCACAGUCCUAUCUUUCUUCUUUAUCUUUUUAUAUAGCUUCUAUCCUCAAGUUUGCUUCUUGGGCCCAAAAUGGCUGCUGGAGCUCCAGAGAGUCCAUUACCAUUACAAUUCCAGACAGGAAGGCAGAAAGGGCAGAAUUGAUGCUCUGAGAGGCUUCUCUAGAAUUCCACUCAAGAACUUCUAUUUCAUUGGCCACCCAUUCUGAGGAAAUAGAACACCUCCAUAGAUUCAGGCUUAUAUUGUAAGGAGGAGAGGGAGACUGGAUAUUGAGUAGGUAAGUAGCAAUCUAUGCAACAGGCUUCAAGCAUAAAUGGGGCUUCCCAGAAAGACAAAGUGAAGAAGGACAUUUCUGGUAAUAGGAACAAAACAUGCAAAGAUAAAAGUCUGUAAAGUAUUUGGUGGGUAUUGGAAACUCAAUAGUCUAGAAAGGCCUUCCAGGUCAACCUUAGUAAAUCUUAUUUUUCUGAGUGGGUUGUGGGUUUGGGGGGGUAUGUGUUGUGGUUAUUGCUGAUGUGGAACCCCACCAUGAAUAAAGGUAAGAGAAGCAACUCUGGUUCAAAGUGCAACAGGAAGAGAACUGUACUUGAAUAAUUAGAAUGUAAGAGAGAGUGACAAGUCCUAAGAGAGUGGUAACUAAAAGAUCAAUAGUACUUCACAGGCAAUGACAGUAGAGCUAUAUUGAAUGGAUUUAGGAUUUCCAAGUGCCAAGCUGAAAGGAAAAGCUGUCCAAAUGGAGGGAACAGCAUUUGCAAAGGCCCAGAGAGAUAGUGAAACAUAAGUGACAUUGAGCCUGAUUCCCCUUUAUCAGAAACUAAAGUUUGUGAAACGGUGUGGGGAAUGAGAUAGGAAAGGUAAGUGGGGCAGGAUCAGUGGAGGACAGUGCAGUUCUAGUAUCUAGCAAGGACGUAACCGUGAUGGAGGCCUCUGAUCUCAACCACUUGAGCAAAGUAGCAGCAAUCAUGCCUUUGUACUGCAGUUUCUUUUAAUAAAAGUAGGAUGCACUUGUAGUCUGGAUUCUCAAGGCACAUAGGCCUAUUGACAAAACACAGGAUCCAUGAGGCCUGAAUCUUGAUCUAAAGUCCACCACUCAGUUUUGGACUAGUCCCUGCUGCCUCCCCUGCCAAAGCAUUUGCAAUCUAACUCUCUGUAGUCACACACACUGUGUAGUCCUCAAGUCAACUCAUCCCAAAGAGUUGGGACCCUGAGGGAAGGCAGUGCUAGUAUGUGCUCUCCGUCUUCUGUGGUGCUCCCUGUCUCCACUUUGGUGCUACAGAUGUGGCCAAUUCUGUGGGAGAAUGAUUUUUAAACUGUAUGUGACUACCCAUAAUGGGUCAUGGAAUCAUUUAGGUAACUCAGAACCAGCAUUUUUUUUAAUGAAAUAGAAUACUGUAUUAGAAUAGGUUAGACUACACUGUGGUAAACAUUUCUAAACUCUUAGUGGCUCAUCAAGCAAAGUUUUAUUUUCUCUCAAAGGCUGCUAAGGAUGUGGUGAUUCUCUAGGGCAAAUGUCCUCCAUGUAGCAACUUAGUGAUGCAAACAGCUCUGAUCUGUGGCUUUACCACCUUCACCGGAGGCCUCCCUGGGUCACUGUAACAGGGAGAGGGUCAGCCUGCUGGCUUCCUGUGUUUCAGUGUAGAAGUGAUGCUAUCCCUUUAUAACCAUAGCACAUUGGCCAGAAUUAGUCCUAGAGCCGCACCUACUUCAGGCACCUGAAAGAAGAGAGCUGGAUAUUGGCAGAUACUAGCUAGCAAUGUCCAGUAUAAACAGAGUAGAAGACAAAUGGAAUGGAACAGAAUAUAUCUAAGUGCAUCACAGAAGGAUUUUAGAGUUAUAUGUGUGUGGUUGAGAAAAUGUUGAGGCAUGUACUAAGUAACAAUUGUAAAAUGUAUUUCUGGCUAGGCGCGGUAGCUCAUGCCUGUAAUUCUAGCACUUUGGGAGGCCAAGGCAGGCAGGUCACCUGAGGUCAGGAGUUCGAGACCAGCCUGUCCAACAUAGUGAAACCCUGUCUCUACUAAAAAAAUACAAAAAUUAGCUGGGCAUGGCAGCGGGAGCCUGUAAUUCUAGCUACUGGGGAGGCUGAGGCAGGAGAAUCGCUUGAACUUGGGGGCAGAGGUUGCAGUGAGCCAAGAUGGCACCACUGCACUCGCCAGCCUGGGCAAAAUCAAGUGAAACUCCACCUCAAAAAAAAAAAAAAAAAAAAAAAUGUAGUUCUAGGUAGAGGCCAGAUGUUUUAAAAAGGCUUCAAAGGGACUACAUCUGAGGAAAAAAGUAUGUCUAGGAGGAGAAGAGAUUUGUGACAUGUGACCCUAUAAAGACAAAGGGCUCUCCUUGUGUCUGCUCAAAGAAAAUAAGUUUCUGAAGUCUCCUGAACAGUCUUCAUUCCAUAGCUCAAAAAUAACCCAGUGUUACAUACCUGGAUUCGUAUAACAAACUCAAUGGGUUACAGUCAACAUUGCUGGGGUGGGAAGUGUGUGUGUAUUCAUUUUGUUCCCUAAAAGAGCUGCAGGGCAUGCAUUCUAACGAAUUUGCUAAAUGGCCAGGAGUCCAUAGAGUUUGGGAAAGUUAGAAGGUGGCCUCAAGAACACCCAGGGACCGGAGAAACAAACAUAAGAAAGGGGAGUUCUAGGCAGGCCCUGGUGACUCAUGCCUAUAAUCCCAGCACCUUGGGAGGCUAAGGCGGGAGAAUUGCU